CACAUUCUACUUUUUUGCUUCAAAUUCAGCAUUUAACUAAGCCUAAUUCCAAUAAGGAAUAUGCACCUCUUUCUUUUACCAUUCUAUAUUUGCCCUACAUGCCCUCUAAUAAAAUUGAAUUUGGCUGAGAAGCCAUUUCUUUAAGAAGGAGACUUGGUUGCUCAGUUGAAGAAUAAAAAUGGCUCAACAGUUUGAUUUUUCUAUUAGUUUUUCUGCCUUUUGCCUGCCCUCUGUCUAGCACUCUUCAACCCCAAAUCUGUGUUCUAGGAAACUUGUCUGAAGAAGAGGGCGGUCCUGAGGCCACUGAGGAGGUUGGAGGCUGGGGCUUCUCUGCAUUGAAAUGUCCCUGGUAGAGAAGGCAAAAGAAAAGCUUUUGAAGAGUGUCUUGAAGUGAAGCAUGCUGCGCUCCCGUGGAGUGGGAAGAAACUGAUCUUCCAGGUUUUGGAGCAGAGAGGCUGAAGAAAAGAUUUAAAUAACAAGAAAACCUGGAGUUGAGCAGCACCUAAAGAUCAGUGAGCAGCUCCAACAUGAUUGUACAGAAGAGCUAACAGGCACUGGAAGUCUAGAGAACAGGCAGAGAUACCCCCUGCACUGUGUAAAAUUAUGAAAAAUGUAUCCAUGAGGUCCUGCUAUCGCAGUGGUAGAAGACUCAAGCCAGGACUUUUAGAGCUUGUAGGUGCUGAGGUAAUCAGGAAUGCUUUCACCAAUAUUCCAGUCCUCUGUCUGAGCACACGGUGAGACGGAACUUCUCAGCUGCCUCAAAGGAUGAAGGAGGAGGCUCCCUCAGCCUGGUUAUCUGGGUGGAGAUGAUACAGAGCAAAGCCCUUCCUCCAAGCCCAUCUAGAGAGGACAUGUCAUAUCGUGGUGGGCUUCCUUCUACAAAGAGGACUCAGAUGUUACUCUUGAGAGCUUAAGAGCCAGAGAGCUGAAAAUGGCAGUCUUAACAAUUUUAUGGAGCCAGGUGGAGGAGCCAAGAUGGCCGAAUGGGAACAGCUCUGGUCUACAGCUCCCAGCAUGAGCGAUACAGAAGACAGCACAUCCAUAGAAGAGACAAUGAGACCACAGGAAAAACAGGUAACCAUCACUGAAACCCUGUGGGACCAGGUGCUGACAGUUUUUAAGGAUAUACAAAAGGAGCUGCAGGAAGAUGCUCGGAUUCGAGGGAUGAGCAACUGCUCCAUGACACCCAUGACAUCAGCACCCAGGACUGGAAGCAUAAGGCCUCCAGAUUCCUUGAUGACCCCAAAGUUGAGAAGAUUGCAGUUCAGCUCUGGAGAGCAGCCAUCAGGAGGCCGUAUCCACAACCUGAAGACACAGCUCUUCAGUCAAUCAGCUUACUACCCUGGACCCUAACUCUACAAUCAAGGAAGAAGGACAUCUCUGCUUCCGCCAGCACAGCUUCAGUUGGGGAAGAUAUUAGCAGACAUCAUCACUGAACCCAGAAGAGAGGGUGGUGCCCAUGAGUGGAGAUGCCAGGGUCUAUGGCUGAAACUGGGAACUUGGAAAUCAAGUGAGACCCAAGCAAGGAAACCAACUGCCAAAGCAAGGAAACCAGCUUGGUUUGGCAAACAGCUGAUGAAAUAAAUGUGACGUAGAAGACUUGCCUUCCUGGUUCUUCCUGGGCUGUGGAAUGGGUAGUGAUAGAAUUUCCAAGUAUGAUAGUGCAUUUGGUUCAAAGAACAGCACUGUAGCAUGGGAGAACCUGCACUAUAAUGUCAUAAACUCAAUCUGACUUUG